AUGCUGUUCUGACAGUUUGAGAUUACUUAUUGUCUUUUCUGGGAAGACAAAAACAUGUCGGAGACUGCUCCACUUGCUCCUACCAUUCCUGCACCCGCAGAAAAAACACCUGUGAAGAAAAAGGCGAAGAAGGCAGGCGCAACUGCUGGGAAACGCAAAGCAUCCGGACCCCCAGUAUCUGAGCUUAUCACCAAGGCAGUGGCAGCUUCUAAGGAGCGCAGCGGCGUUUCUCUGGCCGCGCUUAAGAAAGCGCUUGCGGCUGCUGGCUACGAUGUAGAAAAAAACAACAGCCGUAUCAAGCUUGGCCUCAAGAGCUUGGUGAGCAAAGGUACUCUGGUGCAGACCAAAGGUACCGGUGCUUCUGGCUCCUUCAAACUCAACAAGAAAGCGGCUUCCGGGGAAGGCAAACCCAAGGCCAAAAAGGCUGGCGCAGCCAAGCCUAGGAAGCCUGCUGGGGCAGCCAAGAAGCCCAAGAAGGUGGCUGGCGCCGCUACCCCGAAGAAAAGCAUCAAAAAGACUCCUAAGAAGGUAAAGAAGCCAGCAACCGCUGCUGGGACCAAGAAAGUGGCCAAGAGUGCGAAAAAGGUGAAAACACCUCAGCCAAAAAAAGCUGCCAAGAGUCCAGCUAAGGCCAAAGCCCCUAAGCCCAAGGCGGCCAAGCCUAAGUCGGGGAAGCCGAAGGUUACAAAGGCAAAGAAGGCAGCUCCGAAGAAAAAGUGAAACUGGCGGGACGUUCCCCUUUGAAAAUUUUAAACGGCUCUUUUCAGAGCCACCCA